AGCGCCCAGGCGGCGCACACCAGCAUGGCGGCGCACGGCCAGCCGGCCAGGCGCUCUGCAUAGAAGCGGUGGUGCGCGAUGGCCAGGUAGCGGGUGACGCCCACGCCCAGCAGCAGGAAGGCGGCGUGGAAGCAGAAGAGCGCGGCCAGGAAGGCGAGCAGCUUGCAGCCCAGCGCGCCCGGCGGCGCCCCCGCCGCGGCCGCCGCACGCCGCGCCGCCAGCAUGACGGCCGGGAGGCAGGCGAGCGCGCGCAGCCCGUCGGCCAGGCACAGGUCGAGCAGCAGGGGCUGUGGGGUCACCUUCUCUUCCUCUCUUCUGCCACCCCAAGUCGUCUGUGUUGCGUGUCAUGCAGUGGGACAGCACGUUGGUCCGGACCUCAAGCUACCCACGUUCUAGUCCCGCCUCUGUCAUUUCCUAGAGCUGUGGCCUCGGACAGAGUCUCGCUCUGUCACCCGGGCUGGAGUACAGUGGCCCGACCUCGGUGCACUGCAACCUCCAUCUCCUGUGUUCAAGCGAUUCUCGUGUCUCAGCCUCCCCAGUAGCUGGGACUGCAGAUCCCUCCCUGGUGCCACAGCAGCUGAGUGCGCAUCAAAUCUGAAGAAAAUCUACACAGUACAGACAGUACAGAUAUUUUGGAGUGUAUACAAUAAUAUCCCUCCUGUGACUAGCCUGCCUUUGAGAUGUAGUUAUCAUUUAAUGAGAGGAGAGAGGCGACCACUUUGGGAAGAGGAGAGUAAUGCAAAGGGUGGCGUAUGGAAGAUGAAAGUCCCCAAGGACAGCACGUCCACAGUUUGGAAAGAGUUGCUGUUAGCAACCAUCGGGGAACAGUUCACAGACUGUGCCGCAGCAGAUGAUGAAGUAAUAGGAGUUAGUGUCAGUGUUCGGGACCGAGAAGACGUCGUCCAAGUCUGGAAUGUAAAUGCCUCUUUAGUGGGUGAAGCGACUGUUUUAGAAAAGAUCUAUGAACUUCUGCCCCACAUAACUUUUAAAGCAGUAUUUUAUAAACCCCAUGAAGAGCAUCAUGCUUUUGAAGGUGGACGUGGAAAACACUAAUUGCACUCUGUAAAGAAUUCUUUGUCCUUUGCUGAUUGGUUUUGGAAACGGUCUUAACAGGAGGGAGAGUGAAGAGAAGACUUGCCGAAGCCGAUGCUGGUCAAUUUAGAGUGGGUUUCUGUCCUUGCAGAUGGGCAAUUAGGACUCAAAGUGGCAGGUGGGGUGGGGGGAGAUUGUGUGGGUUUCUACCGUCACAUUACUUGCUUUUUAAAAAAAACACACACAAAAAACUUUUUUUUUGGCUUUCUAAAUUCUCUGUUCUUUUCACUCUGAUUUUUUUUUUUUUUUGCCGUUUAAAAUUCCUUAUUCAGCCUAAUUAUUGUUUUCUACACUCCCCUUUCAUUGAGGCACAAGAAAUGGGUUUCCCUUUAAGUAGCUCUGCUGUACCUAGUUAAUGAGAAUAUGCAUAAUCGUGACAAUACUGCUUUUGAAUACCACACUGUACAAGGAGGAACACUAGCUUGGAGAAAUCUGUCUUCUGAUUAUUUGUUGUGACACAUUCCUAUGUACUGUGAGCUGGGCAUUGUUUUUUUCUGUCCCAGGGAAAAGAAAAACCAUACUUAAUGUGAUUUUGCACUGACAGCACACAAAUCUUUAAUUUUCCUUUUUAAAACAUUUUUUUUUAGUGAUAAAAGGAAAAUAAUAGUUGGAUUGCAUAACAUGAAAACUAUAAUCACAAUUCAGUAUCAGGAUAUAAAUCAAGCUCUAAGUCUUUGGACCCUCUGUGGAAACAUUUCUAACCCGAAUUUUAAUUUGGCCUUUUCAACCAAAGGCUUAGAGUGGUAGCAAGGGAUUUCUUCCAAUAGGAAACCUGAUGUUUCUGAUUUAAAGAGAAGGUGAUAUUUUAAUUGUUUGAAUUAAGCUCCUUGCAAAGUUCGGGUGUGUUUACCCACUUAGGGCUUUCUUUCCCAGUCAACGCUAACACAUUUUGUUAAAUGAUCCCUUUCCCUGCUCACAUUGUGUGUCAUUUCUCAUCAUCAGUAGUCCUCCAGCCUGGGCAGCUGUCCCCACCCUUUUUCAUGUAGGUGCAGGAAGUUAAAUCUCAUUUCCAGGAUGCAUGUGAACAUUUACAAAGUUGAACUUUGAGUGCAUUCUGCUCAUAUGAAUUAUUGGGAUUGUUGAUAUAUAUUGUAUUAUGCUACCAAAGAAAUAUUGGUUUUAUUAGAAGGAAAUGGUCAUCCUCUGGACCAUGGAGACUAGCUCAGAAUACGCUGAUUUCCCUCUCCUGACUUUGCCAAGCCUUUGGCUGCUUUUGCCUGAUAAAGGGCAGGGCCAUCUGAAGACACUUCCCCCAGUCGGCUUUGGAGUCACGGGAGCUAGUGCCUGCUCACACAUUUUUCAAAAGGGCAGUGCACUCAGAACUUCACUGUACCUGGGAUUUUUAAUUCCUCUUGCAGUGUUGACCAGCAGAGAGACUUGAGGCUACUUUAAGCCUCCACUAUGUGUUUGUAGAUAAAAUUCUCCAUUCAAACAUUUUAAAGGACUUUGAACAUUAUCUGCUUAUGGAAGUUGUGCCCUUCACUUGGUUAGUAACCACCUCAGCCAUAAUACUUACCAUCAUAGGUUUCUUAAAAUGCUUUUUUUUUUUCCCUAAACUUGAGUUUCCUUAGUGAUUUCAAAAUGAAGUAUAAGAAUAUCAGAUCCAGUUAGCAAAAGCCUAGGACUUGUUUCUCCAAACAUUGUACUAACAUUCAACUUGUUUUAAAAUUAUGACUCAAGAAUUUUAAAAAAUUAUUCUGGACAUGAAUUAAAACUUUUUUAUAAUAUAAGUAUUUUUCUGAUUGAAAAAAGGAUAUAAUUGACUUCACUCUAAUUGUCAUGUAUAUUUCCAUAAGUAAAUGGAUUUUGAAGUAUUUUUAUUUUUUGAACUUUAUUUAAAGCAUUUGUGAUGACAUGUUCAACUUUUGCAUGUAUGUAGCCUUUGAAGUAAAAAUAAAUAGGAAUGUUAGGCUCACGUUAAUAUUUCUAGUUUCUGUUUAUGAUCAUGGAACAUGACUAGCACACAAAGUAGAUUUUUGCCCCAGUGAACUUCUGCAACUGUUUCUGACCCUUUAGAAAAUACCAACUGUGAGAAGGAUUUAAUUUGCCUAAUGUUAAAAACCUAUCAUCUAAAUUACUUUCAGAGAGGAUUUUGUCAGAUUUUGGUUUGGAAAUUGUUUUAAUUGAAUAUUUAAUCAUAAUAGACUUUGUAUGAACUAAGCUGAUUUAAUCAGUUUAAAAACCUCUCAUUACCUUCUUAGAUUAAAGAAGCUAAUACUGUUUUGAGAUAGAAGGAAAUAUUUUGUGGGGCAUGUGACUUUUGUGUUAAGGCAGUUUACCCAUCUUGGCUGAUGUGGGGAAAGUGCAAACUUCCAGUAGAAUCCCGGUCUUUUCAUCCAAGUGCUUGCAGGGGCAGCCUUGUAGUCUGCAAAGAACCAUGCAGAAACCAAAGAGCUUGCUUUUUUGUCUUUGUAAUUCCUUAGGGUCUGUGAUAUAUGCCAGGAAAUCUGAUUGAAACUAAUAUGCUUUUUAUUCUCCCAUUAUUCCCUAAAUUGUUAUAUCACAGGCACUUGCCUACAUUGGGAAAGUAAGGACAAAUAAUACCCAUUUAAAGUAACUUGCCUAUAUUUUGACUGUCUUUCGUAAGCACUUGCUGAACUGCUGACUUAACUCAGUUUUAAGAUUUCCUCUUUCCCCCCAACUUUUCCACAUUUCUUAAAUGAGGGUGUAAUUUACUGCAAACAUGUACAUUUAAUAUAAUAUUGCUGUUAGAUUCGUGGUACACUUUAUGAAGCAAAAACAUGAAAAGGAAACCACAACUCUAAUAAACUUUAAAUUAAAGAUUAAGAUGACUCUUUCUCACCCCUCUUCUUGAGUUUAGCCCAUGUCUACACCAUGCACACAGUCACAAGACUUUAUAGCUUAGAAACUUUAGGUAUAAUUGGGUCCUAUAGACAUAAUAUACAAUCCACCAACUGAGCCUUGGCCGAACUUGUCCCUUGUUAAAGACGUAGGGCUAGCCAGCCACAGAGCUGGGUAUUGAAGUCGGCAAGUUGUAUCCCGGUGCAGGCGUCCUUAAAUGGAGAGUACUCAGAAUCUGCCAGCCUUAACCUGCCCACUAGCCACCCUAAUCAAGCAUUAAAUAUCUGAUCCAAUCUGGCCACUGGUGUAACUCCGUAAUCAGACAUCCUGUUUGUAAACAGCUCCUCCUUCUCUCCCUCUCCCUCUCAGAGACAGAAGUGGUGCUGGGGUUUGGAGUUUGAAAAUAACCUUCCUAUGACAGGAAGUGGGCUUUUGCUAUUAGUUGCCCAACUCUUAGAGGAUCCCAGCUUGUGUCUUUAGACAAAACUGACAGCCUUUGGAACGAUCGCAUGGUGGCGCUGCCUUCCAGCCAACAGUUCUGGCUCAGCAGCAGAAUUUAUCCAGCUAUGUUUGUAGAAUUUUUUUAAGAUCCUACUGCAUUUUGCUCUUAAGCUUUUAUAAAAAUUUGACGAGAAAAUGUAAAAAUGAUACUUGGCAAUAAGACAUUUAGUUUUCAUGCACCUAAUAAAAAUGUGUCAAAGCUAGAUCGCUCCAGAUGUGCUUAAAAUAUCUCAAAUCCUAGGCUCUCAUUGGCCUUAUAAGUGAUUGGGAAGAAAAAGAAUAAAAUAAACUCACAUAUAGGAGAUAUGGAAAAUAUUUCAUCAAAUAUUAUGCCCAAAGAGAGAAAAUUAGGAGUUGAUUUUUUUUAGCACUCUGAAUAUGGAACUUCCUUUUAAAAAUGUAAUUCUACCCUUCACCUUUCCUACAUUGUAUGUUUCUGUGAGAUUUUACUCAUUACAAGUGAAAGUAGAGGACUGCCUGUGAAUUGUUCACUUCUGAAAAGAAUAUAUUGAGAUCAGUUAAAAUUACUCAAGAGUUUGGUGACUCAGGAUUGUAAAAAGCCUGGAUCUCAACAGCUGGGAGGAGUCAGAGGGUGAAGUGGGAAAAAAUAGGGACUGAGAGGCAACGAAAAGUCCCUUUGAACCUGUGGUCAUUUAUAGCAAUUAGAGUGGGUUGCCCCUCUACUUCUCCCAAGAAGAAAUCCCAAAUAGAUUCCUUUCAUGUCAGAUUAUACUGUUCUGAUUUUAUUUUCUAUUAUUUUUACAUAUACAUCCAAAUCUAAGAAUACUUAUUCAGAUUGGCCCACUCAGGCCAAAAGUCACUGUCUUGUGUUCUAGAAAUUCUUUCAUGUUGCUGACAUAAAUCCAUUUUUAAAAGAACAUUCAGGGACUCUUAGAAUUUUAGAGUGGAAGGGACCUUUGAGAUCAUCUACCAGUGCUUCUCACCCCUUAGCAUGCAGCAAAAUCACUCAGAUACUUACUUAUUAUUCACAUUUCUUGACCCCAGCACUAGAAAUCUGGGAGGAUAUCUGCAUUUUUAACAAGUGCCCUAGUGAUUCUAAUGCUGAUGGUGCUCAGAUCGCUCUUGGAGAACCCCUGAUUUUAUCCAACUCCCACAUAUGACAAAUGAGGAAAGCCUCCCAACCCUAAGCUCUGUCAGGUGACCUGAUUCCAAUGUAUGAUACCAACAAUCUUAUGAAGGCUGGAGAAAACCAUUAAUACUGAGACUUGAGUAGAUGAUGCUCGUGAAUAAGAACUUUAUGGCUGGGACCACAGCAGUCAUGGGAGCCCAUCCCUGGAAGUCCAUAAUAUAAAGCCUUUAAUACAGAGUGGUGGUUUUUCUCUUUUCUAAAUACCAUUUCAGUCUGUUAAGAGAAAAGAAAUUAGUGUUCAGAAAAGUAGUUACUCCAUAUGUGCAGUAACUACUUUUCUAUAAUGUCUUAUGGCAUCUGGGGUUCAGCAUCAUUGAACAAGAUUAAAUGAACGUUAUAGAGCUAUAAAAUUGCAUGUAAAAUAACACAAAACUGUUCAAAUGACUAUCAAAGUAGCCUGGGAAUGAAUUUCCACUAAAAUUAAUUGUCACUUUCAAAACGUAGCUUAGCAAAGCUGUUACUAAACUGGAGAGAUCCUUUAAUACAUAGAAAUGUCAAAAAAAUCAAAUAAGUAUUCCCUAAACGAUGUGAGUGAUAAGCAAAAGUCAUUGCAAAGUCAGUAUUUUUUUGUUCAUCAUUGCUACUGAAAUUCAGAGUUCCAUUGUAUAUGUGUGUCUUGAGUGUACCUUAUUAGAAUAUCCAAUACAAUAGCUUUUGGAUAUUCUAUGCUUUUGUGUCCUUCAGAAAUCAUGAGAUUGAAGGAAUCUGUGUUAAAUGUUUUUGUUUUGGUUGCUGCCUGAAAAAAGUUACCAACUCAUUUAGUGAAAUGCAAGAUUUCUUUAUGAAAAUUUCAAUUUCUAAUAUCGAAGUCAGAUAAUUUUUCUUGAACUUUUAUUUUGGAACAGAUGUUUAUUUCGGAUCUAUUAAAGUGUCAACUUUGCAUUAUAGAACUGAACAUGAAGUAAAUUGAGUGUUUCUGAGUUUUCUAUAGAAAAUUUAUGCUACCUCUCAUCUUUUCACAUACAAAUAAGCAACUUUUAAUGAAGGCUUAGGGUGAAAAUUUUAAUUUUAGCACUUUACAUUACAUGAUGAAUGGUGAAUAUUAAAGGACUUUGAACAUUUUAAUAAACUUACAGUGUUUCUGUUUUCAAAUAGAGGUAUUGAUGCUGUGGAUAUACAUUAAAUUCUCCCCAAAGUUCUCAGACUUUAAUCAGAUAAUGUGGCUUACAACCAUUGUUUUUGUUUUUAAGUUUUAACACUGUCUUUUCAGUAUUCAUUUAAAACAAGUCACCAUGACUUUGAAUAUAUUCUCAUGGAGAAUUUAUUUCAAUGAUUAUAUAAAAGAAUUUCAAAAUUUAAACUAGUGAGCAUACUUUAGCUUGAGACAGCUAACAUUAUUUGUCCCAAAUUUAAAAUCUUACAUUGAAAGUUAUUAAUUCUUUAGAAUAGUCUUACCUGUGUAAGUUGAACCAGGUUUGUUUGAUUAUGUUUUGGAUCUGCUUGUGCCCCCACCCCCCUAUUUUAUACCAUCUGUGCCCUGUGCAGUUGGGGACCCUUUCACAUCUGGCUACAAGCUGGUGUAAUGCCCUUCCUUUUGAUCUGGCUUCAUCUAGUGAUUUGCUCAGUAUUUUUAAGGUCAGACUGAAAACUUUUCUGUUCUAGUUAUUUUUGAUUUUAUAUUGUGUGUUGUGUUUGAUGUUCAGAUACAUGUGAAAGUUGCUUCUAUAAGUCAGUAUUUUUUAUUCCAGCCUUUUGCAGCAAUAAGGUAAGACUAGACUAUACUUUUCUUACUUGAAAAGGUAGUGAUUUAUGUGUUUAGUGCAAAUGUUUAGACUGUUUUGCAAUUUUCUAAUUUGGGACUAUAUUGCUAUGAAUUUGUGCUUCUUCAUUUUUCAGGGUAGUAGUUCACAGGGUUUGUUUAAGUGUUAGUUUGUAGAACUUUAUUUUGAGAUCUUUUGUAAUCUGUUGCUACUAAUUCUCAUUCUGUAUUGAGGUUCUUAUAGUAUAGAAAUGUCAUUUUCAUCCUCCAGUUUAAAAAUUUCAUGCAGUUUAAUCAACCACAUCACUUAAUCAUUAUUAGAUUUCCAGUGUGUGUGUGGUGAUUAGAAUAACCUUGUUUAUUACAACACAUAUUAAAAGUUUCUGUCCAACACCUCUAAUAUGUGUGACGCUGCUAGCAUGGAGUCUGACGCUUAGUAGGUUAUCUGGUAUUCUGAUGGGGAGUAACUGUUGUUAUUUUUACACUUCCCUGUUGAACACAUUUGAUAAUAGGGCUCAUCUGGGUCUCUUAGAAAACGUAUCUUGCUUAUUUUAAUUCUUUUUCUUUACCCUCUAUUAAGAAUGGUUCCGUUUUAGAAUAAGUCAAUUACUCUCGUUGCUCUUUUGUGCUGCAAUUUGCUGGUGAGAUUCAGUUGUCCCCUGUUUCGGCAAGUAAAGUGAAUUUACUCCUCCUUUCUGGCUGUCUAAUAUAUUCCUUUAAAAACAAACAAAACGUACCAACAAACUCUUCUUCCAUUCAUCUGCAGACUUUCCUAUCUCUCCCUGCAGAAACAAGCAAUUCAGGAUCUUAUGUGUGAUGCCUAAUUAAUUUUAACACAGCGAAUUUAAUGAAAUCGUUGAAGAGCAGGGCAUAACACUAGGAAGGCUUUAAAAUUUCAUAAUGUUUCCCUCUCAUAUUUGCAUCUGAUUACUGCCACCAUGCAUUCUGUGUGUACUUUAUCAUCUAGUCGUUAUUGAUGCACUUUUUGGAAUGUGUUCUCGGUUGUUCUAUUAGCAUAGGUUCCUCUGCCUUGUCACCUAACGUACAGUUUUCUUGGAAGCCAAGACCAUGCAUGCCUUUUCUUCCUCAGUGAUCCUUUCGCUGCAGUAACUGCUAUUAAAGAACUUUUAACUGCUUUUCGUUAAUGAAUGCAUAAAAAAAUCUCUGGAAUCCUACAAGACGAUGGUUCUUUUGUUACAUGAAGAAAAGAAAAAACAGUAGCAUUUGCAAGGGCCAGCAAGUUAAAAUAUAUGUCAUUAAAAUAUGUUUCUAUUUCCCAUCAUCUGGCUAGGCUGUGGUGCUGACUAGCUUAUUUCUUGCCAGAGAAAAUAAGUUUAAAUCAUAAGCAUAUUUAACUAGCAAGCAUAAAUCAUAAAUUCUUUAUAAUCGUAAGCAUGUUGAACUCUGGUACCAUUUGUACAGAUGGCAGGGCUAAAUGUGUGUGCUCCUCUAAGCAUUAAAGAUGUGGACAAGCUCUUACUCCCCAAUUUCCUCUUUAACUCAGGAAACUUAAAUCAUUUGUUUUUUGCACAUAUAGGAUUAUAUAAAGUAUGGACCUAGAGAAAGGUUUCAGAUCUUAGGAAACAUUUGAGUUUUGUGAUUCAUGCUUACUGGAAAAGAAUGAUGGAAGUGAAGGUUAAACACUAAAGCCGUGUCCCCUUUUUAAGGCGAAAAUAAUUAGUGUUUCAUGAAGAUAGUCAAGUUAUAAAGGACAAGACUGUUUUUCAGAAUUUUUUUUUUUUUUUGAAAACAAACAUCUUGGAAUCCACAUUUUAACAGAGGUCCAUCAGCUUUCAAAGAGUGUUCCCUAGAAGGGUGGUUCCACAGAAACACUUUCAGAUAUGGCAAAGUUUUCAUUGUAAAAUACAUUUUAAGAAGUAUUUUUAAAAGUGUAAUAAAGCAAUAACACACAGUGACAUGCAUCACAUGGCCAAAUUUUAACAUUUUGGAAGCCAGUAAGUAUAACUUAUGUACUCACUGAUUUUGUUUUAUGAAAUGAAACAAAGGUUUUAUAAAACCUUUUUAUUGUAAAAUAAAGGUACAGAAAACCACACAAAACAAAUGUGUAACUUACUGAAUUGUUACAAGGAGAACACUCUAUAACAGCAGGCCAAGAAAUAGAACUUUGCCGGUCACCCCAGGAGCCCUUUCUUGUGUCCCCGCCCUCUCCACUAAAAUAACCAUUAUCCUGACCUACAGGAGACACUUGCAUUUCUCUCUGGUUUUAUCACAGGUGAUAAACAUCAUUUUACAUAUAGAAUCUUCUCUAACUAUGAACGUUGGUUCAGAAAACUUAUUUGUAAGUCUUUUAAAUGAUGAGUGCAAAAUGACACACUAUAAGCAAUUGAUACCCCCGUAAGUUAGUAACUGGGCAGAAUUUAAUGUGCUUUUGCUGUAGUGUGUGGCUCUGUCCAUAGCUAUAAUAUCCACAAUAACAAUAGCAUGUAUGGAGUUCCAUGCCAUCUAAGCAUAGAGGUUAGUUCUCCCCAACACUCUACGAGGUAGAUGCUGUCAUUGUUGUCCCCAGUUUGUGUAUGUGGAAACAUAUGCAUGAGGUUCAGAGAGGUGAAAUAACUUGCCGAAGGUCACACCAGUAGUCAGUUGCAGAACCAAGAUACAUCUAAGGUACUGUGGCUCCAGCCUGUUCUUCAGUGAGGCUGCCUUGGUGGAAGUUGAAGAUAUGAUGUGCAAGAAUUUUGAGAUUCCUUAUGAGAGUUUGUUUACAAAGAAAAGGUUUUACAGCUUUAAGAAAAAGAUGGAAAAAUCACUGGCCUAGUUCAAACUUUUCAUUUUACAGAUGAAGAAAUGACCCAGAAAGUAUAAAGAAUUCGUUCAAGGUCACACAAGUAGUUGGUGGCAAAGUUGCAGCUAUAUCCCAAAUCUCCUGGCUGUUAAAAUCAAUGAUCUUUUCUUCAUUCCAUAUAUUAUGUGGAAAAAAUGCAUGUUUUCUAACCUGCUUCUUUGCGACAACUCCAUGUAAGCAGAUUUGUCUUAAAACCAGUUUAUAGCUAGGACACACCAUCUACUUGCUUAUUUUCUCAAGGUUUUAACUGGGAAUUAAAAAAUUUAUAUCUGAA